ACACCGGCCCUUCGGGAGCGUCUGAGGAGGCGCGGGCCGCUGCGGGCUCGGGCGCCGCAGCGCGCCGGCCCGAGCCCCUGGACGAGGCCCACGGAGCCGCUCGCCCCGACCCAGCCGCCCGAUGUCCUCAAAAUGGAGGCAGCGGGGGCGGCGGCGUGAAGAAAGCGGCGCUGUGGGCGCGGGAGUAGGGGCCCGGGCGGAGGCGGUGGCGGGAUGGGGCUGCUGCUCAUGAUCCUGGCGUCGGCCGUGCUGGGUUCCUUCCUCACGCUCCUCGCCCAGUUCUUCCUGCUGUACCGCAGACAGCCCGAGCCGCCGGCGGACGAGGCCGCCCGCGCGGGCGAGGGCUUCCGCUACAUCAAGCCAGUGCCGGGCCUGCUCCUAAGGGAGUACCUUUAUGGCGGCGGCCGGGAUGAGGAGCCCUCCGGAGCGGCCCCUGAGGGCGGCGCGACCCCCACCGCGGCCCCCGAGACCCCCGCCCCGCCGACGCGGGAGACUUGCUACUUCCUCAACGCCACCAUCCUAUUCCUGUUCCGGGAGUUGCGGGACACCGCGCUGACCCGCCGCUGGGUCACCAAGAAGAUCAAGGUGGAGUUCGAGGAGCUGCUGCAGACCAAGACGGCCGGGCGCCUGCUGGAGGGGCUGAGCCUGCGGGACGUGUUCCUGGGCGAGACGGUGCCCUUCAUCAAGACCAUCCGGCUCGUGCGGCCAGUCGUGCCCUCGGCCACCGGGGAGCCCGAUGGCCCUGAAGGGGAGGCGCUGCCCGCCGCCUGCCCCGAGGAGCUGGCCUUCGAGGCGGAGGUGGAGUACAACGGGGGCUUCCACCUGGCCAUCGACGUGGACCUGGUCUUCGGCAAGUCCGCCUACUUGUUUGUCAAGCUGUCCCGCGUGGUGGGAAGGCUGCGCUUGGUCUUUACGCGCGUGCCCUUCACCCACUGGUUCUUCUCCUUCGUGGAAGACCCGCUGAUCGACUUCGAGGUGCGCUCCCAGUUUGAAGGGCGGCCCAUGCCCCAGCUCACCUCCAUCAUCGUCAACCAGCUCAAGAAGAUCAUCAAGCGCAAGCACACCCUACCGAAUUACAAGAUCAGGUUUAAGCCGUUUUUUCCAUACCAGACCUUGCAAGGAUUUGAAGAAGAUGAAGAGCAUAUCCAUAUACAACAAUGGGCACUUACUGAAGGCCGUCUUAAAGUUACGUUGUUAGAAUGUAGCAGGUUACUCAUUUUUGGAUCCUAUGACAGAGAGGCAAAUGUUCAUUGCACACUUGAGUUAAGCAGUAGUGUUUGGGAAGAAAAACAGAGGAGUUCUAUUAAGACGGUUGAAUUAAUAAAAGGAAAUUUACAAAGUGUUGGACUUACACUUCGUCUUGUCCAGUCAACUGAUGGGUAUGCUGGGCACGUCAUCAUUGAAACUGUGGCUCCAAACUCGCCUGCUGCAAUUGCAGAUCUUCAGCGGGGAGAUCGACUUAUCGCCAUUGGAGGUGUGAAAAUCACAUCAACACUGCAAGUGUUGAAGCUUAUCAAGCAGGCUGGUGACCGAGUCCUGGUGUACUAUGAAAGGCCUGUUGGCCAGAGUAAUCAAGGUGCAGUGCUGCAAGAUAACUUUGGCCAGUUGGAAGAAAACUUUUUGUCAAGCUCAUGCCAAUCGGGUUAUGAAGAGGAAGCUGCCGGGUUGACAGUAGAUACUGAAAGUAGAGAGCUGGAUUCUGAAUUUGAAGACUUGGCAAGUGAUGUCAGAGCACAAAAUGAGUUCAAAGAUGAGGCACAAUCAUUAAGUCAUAGUCCCAAACGUGUUCCAACAACACUUUCUAUUAAACCCCUUGGAGCUAUAUCACCAGUUUUAAACCGUAAAUUAGCUGUAGGAAGUCACCCACUACCACCGAAAAUUCAGUCCAAAGAUGGAAAUAAACCUCCACCCCUAAAAACUUCUGAGAUAACAGACCCAGCACAAGUGUCAAAACCAACCCAAGGAUCUGCUUUCAAACCACCUGUGCCACCACGACCACAAGCGAAAGUUCCUUUGCCUUCCGCCGAUGCUCCAAAUCAGGCAGAACCAGAUGUUCUCGUUGAAAAGCCAGAGAAGGUGGUGCCACCUCCUCUUGUAGAUAAAUCUGCUGAAAAGCAAGCAAAAAAUGUGGAUGCCAUAGACGAUGCAGCUGCACCUAAGCAAUUUUUAGCAAAGCAAGAAGUGGCCAAAGAUGUCACUUCAGAAACUUCCUGCCCUACUAAGGACAGUUCGGACGACCGUCAAACAUGGGAAUCAUCAGAAAUUCUUUAUCGUAAUAAGCUAGGAAAAUGGACAAGAACCAGAGCAUCCUGUUUGUUUGACAUAGAAGCCUGUCACAGGUACUUAAACAUUGCAUUGUGGUGCAGGGAUCCUUUCAAGUUGGGAGGUCUCAUCUGUUUGGGGCAUGUUAGUUUAAAACUUGAAGAUGUGGCUUUAGGAUGCCUAGCUACAUCAAACACGGAAUACCUUUCCAAAUUGAGACUGGAAGCCCCCUCACCUAAGGCUAUAGUCACUAGAACCGCACUACGCAAUCUGAGUAUGCAAAAGGGAUUCAAUGACAAAUUUUGCUAUGGUGACAUUACUAUUCACUUCAAAUAUUUGAAAGAAGGAGAAUCAGACCACCAUGUAGUUACUAACGUAGAAAAAGAAAAAGAACCCCAUUUGGUUGAAGAAGUUUCUGUUCUCCCUAAAGAGGAGCAAUUUGUUGGACAGAUGGGUUUAACAGAAAACAAACACAGUUUUCAGGAUACUCAGUUCCAGAACCCAACAUGGUGUGACUACUGUAAGAAAAAAGUUUGGACUAAAGCAGCUUCCCAGUGUAUGUUUUGUGCUUAUGUUUGCCAUAAAAAAUGUCAAGAAAAGUGUCUAGCUGAGACUUCUGUUUGUGGAGCAACUGAUAGGCGAAUAGACAGGACACUGAAAAACCUUAGGCUGGAAGGACAGGAAACCCUCUUAGGCCUGCCUCCUCGUGUUGAUGCUGAAGCUAGCAAGUCAGUCAAUAAAACAACAGGUUUGACAAGGCAUAUUAUCAAUACUAGUUCUCGUUUAUUAAAUUUGCGUCAAGUCUCUAAAACUCGCCUUUCUGAACCAGGAACCGAUCUCGUAGAACCUUCACCAAAACACACACCCAACACGUCAGACAACGAAGGCAGUGACACGGAGGUCUGUGGUCCAAACAGUCCUUCUAAACGGGGAAACAGCACAGGAAUAAAGUUAGUGAGAAAAGAGGGUGGUCUGGAUGACAGUGUUUUCAUUGCAGUUAAAGAAAUUGGUCGUGAUCUGUACAGGGGCUUGCCUACAGAGGAAAGGAUCCAGAAACUAGAGUUCAUGUUGGAUAAGCUACAGAAUGAAAUUGAUCAGGAGUUGGAACACAAUAAUUCCCUUGUUAGAGAAGAAAAAGAGACAACUGAUACAAGGAAAAAAUCACUUCUUUCUGCUGCCUUAGCUAAAUCAGGUGAAAGGCUACAAGCUCUAACACUUCUUAUGAUUCACUACAGAGCAGGCAUUGAAGAUAUAGAAACUUUAGAAAGUCUGUCUUUAGACCAGCACUCCAAAAAAAUAAGCAAGUACACAGAUGAUACAGAAGAAGACCUUGAUAAUGAAAUAAGCCAACUAAUAGACUCUCAGCCAUUCAGCAGCAUAUCAGAUGACUUAUUUGGCCCAUCCGAGUCUGUGUAGCAGACAGGUCUAUUUAAGCUUUCAAAUGAACAGGGUAAAGUUGCAUCUAAAGUACCACAGAUACAACCAUGUUUAAAUCCUCGUAUGCACUCUGGCCUGCUUCUCCAGUUACUUGCUUGUGUAAGAACAAAAAUGAGAAAGGUUGUUUUCCAGUAAAAACAUGACCAGCUUACUAAUUGGUUGUUUUGGAUUGCAUUUAUAGCUAUGCUUUUUUGGGUUUAUACUGGGAAUUUAUUUUUACUAAAUUAUUUAACUUUUCUAAUUAUGUAAUUAUGUAAGCUAGCUUUUCAUGUUUAUGUAUGUAUGGUGUCCCCUUGUGUUAUUUUUCUUCCUCUUGGUUUUUGAAUUAGUGUUAAAUAGAAUACUGUCUAGAUUCUUAAAAUAUUUUCAUUUCCAUCAUGGUUAUAACAAAUUUGCUGCAUGCCCAAACUGACAACAGCAAUCACUGAGGGAACAGGUUUUGAAUCUUUCUUUUGUGUUAUGAAGUUUAUCGUCUCUACUUGCUUGAGAUUUUUGUUAUUUUGGGGGUUUGGGGGUGCUUUUUGUUUUGUUUUUGCCAAAUGUAACAUGAAAGCAGAUGCUGCAGCUUUAGUCUGUUAUGCUGAUUUAGUAAAAAAAAAUUUUUUACAUAUAUUGCUUGCUUUCGAUGCUUCUGUGAAAUUUUUUUCUAAAGCUUUUGUGCAGCUGUAUGGUAAAAAUAUGGUGAUUAAUUUGAAGAGCUUACAUUGAAAGACAAUGUAAUAGGAAAUAAAUGUAGAUUGCAGUUGGUCAAGAAUUUUGUAGAGAGGAUAACAAGACUUAAUUACUGAAAAACAGUAACAUAGCAUUUUGAAAUAUAAUCUUUUAAAAUAUUGAUGCUUUCCUUUUAAAUGGAAAUUUAAAUUUUAUAAUUAAAAGUUUAAACAUUUAUGAUAAUUUUCCUCAUCAGUUCUCCCAUAGGAAAUAAAGCAUGUGAAAGGGUAUUUAAAGUUUUGGAGGACUCUUUUUAAAAUGACUGUGUUGAUAACUAGUUUGGGCUGGUUUUGUUUUAGAAAAAACAUUUUCAUGUAGGAGUAUUCUGUGAAGGAAAGGAAUCAUGCAAAAUAUACUUUUUGCUUUGGCGUCUUACAGUUGUAAAGGAAUGGUGAUCAUUCUGAAUACUUCUGUAGUGAGUAUUCAUUAAGAAAAGAAUGACAAAAAUAGUAUUCAUACAUAGGAAUUGGGACCAGUUCUCUGAAAAUGAAGAUAUACUCACACUGGGUCCAUUUUACGGGUCCCAGUAACAUUUGACUGAGGGAAAACAAGUAAGCUCGACUGUUGUUGGGGUACCUUAAUGGUUUCGGUCUGUUAUAUACCUAUAAAAUAGACAAGUAUAUGUUUGUCCCUUUGUAGGUAACUGCUAUGAUGAUUGCUAUAUAGUGAAACUGACAUGAGUUUAAAACUAGAUGGAGCAGCUUUUAUUGCUGGCAGGAAAAAGCAUGGUGUAAUAUUAAGGACUGGGGCCCAGGUCUAGACUCCAGGACUCCAUAAAAGAGUUUAAGUUCAAGCCCUUCCAUUAAUGAACUGUGUAAGCAUAGGCAGUUACAAAAGGACCCAUCUCUAAAAUGGGAAUAAUAAUACUUUACCUCCCUCACAGUAUUGUUGUGAGGGAAACAAUAGCAUAACUGCAAAAGUGCUUUGAACAGUAAAAAGAUAUACAAGUAAAAGGCAUUAUUUAUAUGAGUAAGAAAGACAUUUUUGAGGGGAGAAAAGUUAUUCCACUUUAAAAAUCAAUAGCCAAGUCUCAUGCCUUUUGUUACUUUAGUAAGCGAAAAUUUCAGGUACUAAAUACCUUUCUUAGCCAAGUUUAUAACAAAAACAUCUCAGUAUACUUCAUUACUUAUUUAAGCGUGAUGUCUUUUUUUUUUUUUUUUUUUUUUUUUUUUUUUUUUUUUUUUGAGACAGAGUCUCGCUGUCUCCCAGGCUGGAGUGCAGUGGCAUGAUCUCGGCUCACUGCAAGCUCCGCCUCCCAGGUUCACGCCAUUCUCCUGCCUCAGCCUCCGGAGUAGCUGGGAGUACAGGCGCGGCUAAUUUUUUGUAUUUUUAGUAGAGACGGGGUUUCACCAUGUUAGCCAGGAUGGUCUCGAUCUCCUGACCUCGUGAUCCACCUGCCUCGGCCUCCCAAAGUGCUGGGAUUACAGGCGUGAGCCACCACGCCCGGCCACGUGAUCUUAUUUUAAAAGAACACUGCUAUAGAAGAAUUUACACACCAAAUUCCCUGAAAGCUAAAGUAUUGUUCCAUAACUUACACUUGAGGCAAUCUGCUCAGUGUGUAACCACUUUAUAAAAAAUAACUUACCAUUGAUAACCUGGAAGGUGGACUACUUGUAAGUAGCUGGUGUUUAUUGAUUAAACCAUGGAAGUUUUCAUGAUACCCAAGCAUGUUGCUGAAACUGAUGCAUUUGAAAGAGCUGUUGAAAUAAUGCAAAACUUUGGUUUUAUAAGAAUCUACUCAUGUUUUAAAAGUAUUUAACUCUGUAGACCACAAUUAUAGAAAGCUCAGUAAUGCUGCUAAUGACAUUUGUAAACUAUAUCUGUAAUGUAGUGCAAUAUUUUUAUAUUUCACUGGGAGAGGCAGUAGAGACAUCAUAGUUGUACUUUAGUGCAAGUGGGGGAACACUCCAAAUAGCCUAGAGUAUAGUAAGGUACAAAGCUUCAAUGAAAAAAGCUGUAUUAUAUUACAUUACUGAUGUAAUCUUGCUGCCAUGCUAUGUAUCAAUAGCUAAAAAAUAAUAAUAAAGACUACCACAGAAAACAAGAAUAUCUUCAUUUAAUGAAAUCUUUAAAAAAGGUGAUUGCUGCAUCUCUAUGGAAUUAUCUUCUGGUAUAAUUUGGCCAUGCAGAAAAGCAUAACAAAGUCCACUUUUCCUAAACAAAAUUGCUGUUUUGCAGACUGCCCCAAAACAUUUUUUUACUAUUGUUUCCUUAUGGAUUAUCAAGUUUAUGGGUUUCCUUUGGCUAUGUAUUAGUAAUUAGACUUUAAAAUAUAUUUUCUACAUUAGUAUUAGCUGAGUGAAUGGCUUAGACAAACUGAGCAACAUUUUAGCAUUAUUAGCAAUCAUAAUAGGCUAUACUUCUUCAUAUCAAGCCUUAUAUUCAAUAUCAGAAGUACUUGAAAUAAGUGGCUAUUUUGUGAUGCUGGGAGGAGAAAACACAACCUAAAAAUUUUGAGGGGUACUAUCAAGUUCUAAAUGUAUAGCUGAAUUUUUUUUAAAGCAAUUUGGAAAUAUUUGGCUCUUAAAAAUAAGAUAAAUAAUAAAAUGUUAAGUCCCCUAAAAGUGAAUAAAUUUUAAAUACCUACUUUUAAAAAUACUGUCUUCUAAAUUGACAUAAUUGCUUUUCUUACCAAAAGAAGGAGAGGUUCCCCUAAUUCCUUUUGGGCCAUAGAUCCGCUUUUAGGAUCUGAUUAAAGAUGUGGACUUUCACCGCAGGAAGAUACCCAUGGGCACACCAUUCAAAAUGUAUCAGAUUUCAACGGUUUUACAAACUCCCCCGGGAUUAAGUCAAAUGGGUGGAUAUUACAGCUGUUUUCAUCAGAUAUGGUUAUUUGUUGACAACCAUCAGGACAACAAUGUUUAUAGAUGGAAGGAUAACUUCCUGGUUUUUUUCCACAUUGAAUGUGGCUAGUUACAUAUCUCAAUUUAAAAUAAAUUGUGGAAAGCCAAAAAAGUAUGGUCAAGCUAACCUGGGGUGGCUUUUACCUGAUGCCUACAAGCACAGAAAAAUAGUUUUUAAUUAAAUAUCCACAGUCAAAAUGAUACCUUAUGUAUUUUAUUCCAACAACAUUUGGUUUAUAAAGGAAUACAAACAGGCACAAAACAUGGUUCAGAAGAUUUAUUAAGUAAACUUGCUAAAAUAUGGACAGAUACACUUAGCAGUCAAACAGUUGAAUAUUCAUUGCUACCUCAUUAAAGUUUUUGUAUCUGUAUUACCAGGUCCAAACAUAAAAACCACCUCUGUUCAAAAAAUAAAUGUUCAGAGAGCUGUAUGUUCUUUGUUCUGGUAUGUACAUUUUAAAAAAACACCUCUUUCCAGUCUUGCUAACCAAGAAUAUUAGUCAUAUAAAAGAACUUAGAAUUUUUUUCCCCAAGUACAAGCUAUCUUUUGCUCCAAAACAGUUCUGAAGGUUUUAUUUAUAUUUUAUCUUAUCCCGAGGGACCAACAGCAGGCAUACCUUUGCCAGGCCUUCUUGCAGAAAGACACAGAGCCGUAAAGGCAAAAAUAAAAUUGCAAUAAAGUAUAUGGUAUUGGGGGCAGGGAGAACCAGAAACCCUCAAAGAGAACCAAUUUGUAGCACGUUCUUUUUUAAGGCUCUACCCCUGUAGAAGUAAGAAACUAGCCUGCCUUUUUAGCCAUAUGAGAGUUUCCUCCAGAGCCAUCUUCCAAAGUGGCAGACUUGGCCAAGUUGCCCAAUGCCAAAUAAGUGAGUUGGAAGUUCGUUUGCUUCAAACACACUGCACUUAGAAACCAGACUUGAAAUAAUCGAAGCCCCACAGAAAAGCUUCAUGAAACGAAGUGUUACUUUCCUAGAGAAUAAGAAAGUCACAAGAUUGAGGAGUCUGUUCUAAAGUUCUUUGCUCCUUGAUGUCGAAGUUAACACAAACACAAUCUUAGCUUAACGAAACUAAGUAAUUUUUGUUUAUGAUUAUAGAACUGCAGGAUUCACAAGUAGUAUUAGAGACAUUCCACACUGCACACUCCAGUCAUAUCUCUUAACAAAAUGACAUAAAUUGACAAUGUUCACUAACAGUAUUUGCUGUUACACUGAAAAGGCACAUCAAUGUUGUCAUGCUUAGAAAAAUACACAACACUGCACACUGGAUGAUAUAGUUAGCACAUACAUUUUUAGAUGUUCCAUUUUUCUUUUCUGCCUGAUCACUAUUAUUUUUACUUCUUAAUAUAUGAUUCAAGACAUAAUUUCAUUCUUCAUUUUCAUUUAAAAUUUGUCUUCACAUUGAUGUGAACAACUUUCAGGAGUCUAAAAAAUAGUAGUUUCAGACAACCUAAAAUAAAUAUAUUCCUAGAAAACACUUGGAUGACCUGCAAACAGAUCAAAGAUAUAGUCAGAUAUUAAAGUCAGAGCAGCUGUUUUCAGCUUCUUGUUUCCUUUUCUAAAACUUGAAGUAGAUGGCGAUUAACCUUAUCAUGUUUAAACAACCUUGACAGUAUAAGGUACAUGUACCCUCAAUUUUCUUCAUCCAGUAAGACAAGUAUGCAUCUUAAAGGGAAAGCUUUUAGUUCAUAACAAUAUGUUUGGUUGCUUUUCUCUGCUUUCGGAACAUUUACUGUUUUUCCUUUAUUGGCUUUAGUGUUUGCUGCCAACCAGAUAACAUGUUAACAUAUAAUUUACAACUCUCUCUAGGUAGGUGAUUACAUAGAAAACUAAUGCCAGCUAAGAUUUAUGGAUUCAAAAGAUAACUGACACAAGUUCUUGUCCUCUACACUUGAGAGAACUAGCUGUUUAACGCAUAAAUAUAUUGAUAGUAACUACAAGUUAAAUAACAUUCAGUGUCACUAUAUAACAUGCUGUCUUACUUGAUUCUGUUUUUCAGACUUCAUUCUAGUUUCUCUUUGUUGGAAGAGUCUCAGAGAUAAUGUGUGCUUUAAUUUUAAACACUCAUUACCAAUAUGAUUUUUGCCCAAAUGUUUGUUAAUGUAAGUUAAAAAAUUAUAUUUGGUUUGGAUUCAAAUAUUUAUAGAUUUACACAAUACCUAUUUCAUCAAAAUAUAUUGUAUGAUAUUUAAUAAAAUUAAAUACAUAAAAUAAAGUUUCAACACUAUUUAUACAAACCCCUAGAAAAGCUUCUUUUUCUUUAUAAGGCUGUUGGCAAUCGACCAUAACCAUGGAAAGGAAAUAAUAACCUUUGGUUUUACUCUUUCACCAGGGAUGGAUGGUAUGACUAAGACAGUUCUGGAUGAGUUGUGUCACUGGAAACACUGUUUUAUACAAUUAAACACUUUGAUGAUUUUUGAGGA